AAUGGACCGAAGAGCUCCGGCGUGAGGGGCAGGGGUGCAGGAAGGUCUCCUGUGGAUUGAGCGGCCUCAAGUCAACUUGGGCAAGAGGGGAUGGUGGGGUGUUCUUGGUUAGGAGUCUGCGCUGUGGAGCCAGCCCUGGGGUGCUCCCUCUGAGGCCUUGGGUGGGACAGGCCCUUCUAAGCUCCUGUCCUCAUUUCUAAAACAGGGAACCUAAGUCCCAGGGCUGCAGUGCAGAUUAAAUGGCAGGACGCCUGCUGAAGGCUGCAAGUGUUUACAGGAUCACCCUGCCGCCGCAUGAAGAGGAGGCUGUCGGGCGUGAGGACGAGGCAGAAUAAGGGUGACCAGUUGGGAGGUGGCAGGGCCCAUCUGAUUAAACAGACCAGGCCACUCACUGUGGAGUGGACCAAGGAUACUCCUGUCCCUGAGCCCAUGGAGCUAAGGUCUGAUGCCAGCCACAAGGAGAAUGUGUCCCCAAAGCCUGCAGCGCUCCCGAAGCCAGAGCAACGAAGAUUCCGGAGGAGCCUGGGCAUCGGCCUGAGUGGUAGACAUGACCAGUGGGUGCCCGGGUGCCAGGUGGAGAGGGGAGGGCCUGCUGCCACACCCUCCCCAGGGGCAGUGCUAGACCAGGAGCCCUGCCGAGUCCAGACCAACCUGGCCAGCCCUGGUCCCCGCCUGGGCCUAGCUCUGAAGGACACGACUGGCCAACUGGUCAAUUCAAGCUUCUGGCAACAGAGCAACCUGCAGUCCCUGGCCAGGAGGCGCCAAGGGAAGGCCCGAGAGUUUGCCAUCCAGCAGAGCAACCUGAGCAUCAACGAGACCAGCAGCCCCCACCUCUGCCCAGAGCCUGGGGGAAGCUCUGGGCCCCACAAGCUUCCCUGGGGUCCUCUCCUAUCCCAAGAGCCACUGGCUCGCCCAUCUUCCUGCCUGAGGCAGUCCGGGCUGCCGGCCCCAGGCACCCCUAGCGGGGACUUCAGGCCCACUGAAGCCUUUGCCCCUCUCGAUGGGCAUACACAGCCAGGCCUCAGAUCCUGGGGUGGUCUGGGGAGCUGGAGGUCCAGGCUGGUGGGGGAACCUCUCACCCUGGAGGACCUGGCUGUCCCCAGUCAGAACCAGACUCAGGCCCCAUCCCGUGCUGCCGUCCACCAGCUGCUGGCUUCUGUACAUUGCCUGGCGCAGGAGGCAGCCCGACUCAGGUGCCAGGCUCCCCAGGAACCCCCCGGUGCUGUGCAGCAGGACCUCUGGACCGGCGGCGGCCAGCCAUUCUCCGCCCACCCCCAGCCCAGCCAGCCUGUCCUUGCUUCCUCGGAUGGGAGGAGGAGACGCCUUCGAGGCCACAGGGAAACUGCGGCUUUCUUGGAGACCCCGGCUAGUCUCUCAGACUCUUGGGCACAAAGCAAGCUAAUGUCACCUGAGACCACUUUGGGGACACGGACCAAGGAUUCCCUUAAUCCUGAGCAGGGGCUCCCUCCUGCCCACCCCCUAGGGUCAGGGGACAGCUGCUCCCCCUGGUCUCAAGAUGGCAGGGCACAGAGGGGUGACCCCAGUCUCCCUCGAGGGGUGGGAAGCAGGGGGACCGACCCCUGUUCCUCAGCCUUCUCCAACACAGCCUGGGGAGUCUCACCCAAGCAGAAAGGAGAGGAGGGGGCCCCGAGGGAGCGGGUCCACAGGGAGGAGGAGAGGACAGCUUUCCAUCUGUCAGACACAGUCCCAGCGAGCAGUGCGUCGAAGAACAAGGCACAAAACAUCACAGCCCCAGAGUCUGAGGCAAUCUGCUGGCAGCUGUUGUCCAGAUGUUUUCGAUCCUGGAGGCACUUGGUGAAGAGGCAGCGGGAGCCAGCGGCGGCGGCAGUGGCACUGGGCCGCUGGCAGCUGUUGCGAAAGUGCCUUCAGGCCUUGUGGCUCCGGGAGGCUCAGCUGGAGGCAGCAUGGGGGCAGUACACAAAGGUUCUGCUGGUCCGGAGCUUCCGAGAGUGGAGAAACCUGGCUUUACAGCAGAAACAAGUACAGCCCCACAUGCAGGCUGGGCCAGGGUCCCCGCCCUCCAGGAGAGCCCAGGGCAAAGGCCUCUCCUUGGGAAGAAGCACAGUGGUGGACCCCGCCCAGAGAAGCAGGCUGGAACACACCAGUCCAGGAAGUCUGAGGGAGGAGGAGAUUGCUCAGCGGCUUCUGUCACAUCCUAGGCAGAGAACAGACAGCAGACACGAGAGAGUCCAGAUCCUGCAGGCCCUGCAACUGGCUGUGUUCUUCCUGUGGUGCCAACAGAAGAAACGGGCCAGACAGGAGAGGGAGACUCUGCGGAAGGCCACCAGGGCCACACAGAGGACAGGGAGCUUCCCCCAGGCCUGGCACUCUACUGCUGCAGGUGUAGCCUGGGUGGCCCCACUGAGCCCCCAGCACCAGAGAGCUUGGCUGUGCAGGUGCUUCGGGGCGUGGCAGCAGUUCGUGCAAAGAGGGUCCCGGUACCGAGACCACCUGGCUGACCGCCGGACGGGGACCCUGAGGAAAUGCCUGGAACAGUGGGUGCGGAUGAAGCAGCUCCGGGAAUCAGAUGGGGCAAAGGUGACCCAGCUGUCCCUCUGCCGGCAGAAAGCAGGACGUGAGGCUGUCUACACCGCAGGCCCUGGAGCCUGUGGCCUGGGUGCAGUGGGCCAGGCCCAGGGGCAGCAGGAGCAAGGCCGGGGCUCCCUGCAGGAUGCCUGCUGGACACUGGCCCUCUGCUGGGCGCUGCUGCUGUGGAAGAUGCGGCUUUUCCAGCGCCAGUGGGCCAACUCCUUCUUCCAGGGCCUGCAGCAGCGGAUGCUGCAGCGCAGCCUGAGAUGGUGGCACUUGAGGGCACUGGGCCCAGAUGCCACAUCAAGCUGCACCAAGACCCCCUCGGCUCUGGAGCCACUGAGCAGCAGCACACUCCAAGACUCUCUGGAGAAGGUUCCCAGGGCCCCCACCCUCCCGGACACUCUCCAGGGGAGCCUUCUGUGGGCAGCUGGGCAGCGGCAGCAGGGGCAGUGCCUUCUGCUCUGGCAGGCACGGGCCCAGCAGUUCCAGGGCACAGCCAGGUGGUACCAGCAUACCCGCCAGAGGCGCAUCUUCCUCAGCUGGAGCCGCUGGGCAACAGCCCAAUGGGCCUGGAGAGAGCUGGCUUCCCACCGGGCCUGGGAUCGGACCUGCAGGGCUGUGCUGGGCCUGUGGCGUCAGCGGCUGCUGCAGUCACGGCUGGUGGAGUGGUGGGCCCAGGAGCGGGGCUGGCGGCUGGCACGAGAUGCCCUAUGCCACUGGCACUCCUGUUGGCAGGGGCAGCAGUUCCUGCAUGAAAAGUGCCAGACAUGGGUGCAGGUCCACCUCCAGGGCCUGCAGAAGGUGGUGUUCCGGAGCUGGCAGCAGGCAGCAGCUCAUCAGAGAUGCACAGUGACCCGGCCAGAGCAGCUGCUACUGCAGAGCUACUUCCAGGCCUGGUGUGAGGUUGUAAGAGACACGGGGGUGCUCCGGGCCCAGCAUCAAGCCUUUCAGGAUGGCCUGAGGAGAAGAGCACUGGGGGCCGUGUUUGCCACAUGGCGGGAAGCCCAGGAAGUGGCAGCCGGGGCACAGGAGCAGCGUGUGGCCCAGGCCUCCCUUGCCCGCUGGAGAAGCUGCGGGCAGCAAGGCCAGGAAGAUGGGCAGCAGAAGAAGGCCCGGGCCCCACAGGCCUUCCCAGCAUGGCCAGUGGCCCCGGGCAUGCACCAUGAGGCCCAGCAGCAGGCAGGAGAGAGCGCUGGGGCCCAGGCAGCCCAGUGCUGGACUUGGUGCUGGGCUCUGUGGGUGCAUGAGUCCUGUCGGGGCCAGGUCAGCCGAGCCCAUGCUUCCUGGAAGCCGCGAGCCUGGGUCCUAGAGGCCUCGGUGCAGUCGGCGGUGCGCGGCGGUGUCCAGCGAGCCAUCCUCACCCAGCUCCGGCCGGCUGAGCUCAGGCGCUUCCUGCGGACAGUGCAGCUCAGGGUGCGGCUGGGACUGCCAGGGGCCGGCAAGACCCGCAGCUGCUGGACACAGGCCACAGAGCUGGUGCCUCCCGCGCCAUCACUGCAGUGCAGCCUGGGUGGACGGAGGAAGCCAAGGGGAACGGCCUGGGCUCAGAGGUGCAGGGAACAUUCCCUCUGCCCUGCCUUCCAGCUCUGGCCACAGUGGCCUGGACAGAGUAGCUGGGUCCCAGGCCUGCCCCUGUGGACGAGGGACCAGGGACCAAGAGCGCACUCCAGCCCUGAGCCCAGAGCCUGCAAAGCCCAAAGCAAGGCCCAUAAACGGAGGCUACGUGCUCGUUCCUGCAGGAUCCUGGAAAAGCAGGCCCAGGCCCAUGGCUCUGCCCUCCUUCUGGCCCUGAAGGGUCACGAUGCUCUUGGCCAUCAGGAGGAAGUACCUGCAGCGCCGGUGCCUCGAGGCACUGCUUCACGGGCUGCGGGGUUCCCAGCAGGCCAGGUGCCUGGCAGUGGCAUGGCAGCACUGGGUGGAUGCCCAAGGGGCAGAGCAGCUGGUGCGGACCCUGCUCAGGGAGUGGCACCUGAGAUGGGCCUGGCAGACGUGGUGGCAGCGGAUCCUGCGACUGCGAGUGGCUCAGCAGUUACAGCAGCAGGAAGAUGGGUGGGUCCUUUCCCAGGUACUGCCCUCUUCCCUGCAUUCCACUCAGCCAGCCUUCCAGAAGUCUGUGCCACAGCCACGCACCGUGGAGCUUUCCCUGCUUGCCAGCCCCGGGGCCCCUUCGUUUUCAGGGGAGGGGGUCAGUUCCAUUACAGAACACACAGGCUGGAUGCUGGAGCCCUUGCUUUGAUUUGUGGCCCCAGCUCAGGCCAGGCCCACCCGGUCCAUCAGUUUGCGAAGAAGGUGUGGCAUGAGGCAUGGCUGCCACUCACACUAGCCCAUGGAGGGCCUGGGUCCUGAGCGCCCCCUCCCUCAUUUGCUCUGCUCUGAGUACAGCUUCCCAGCUCACCAUCAGAUCUAUUCUGAGCUUGUGCAUUUGGCCUAGGCAAGACUGGCUGGCUGCUUGGGGCAGAGGGAGGGGCCCUGGGGACAAAAGGAGCUGGGUACAGGGGUUGCUCUAGCAGGCACAGCACAGACCCCGGAGAAAGCCCACAACAAUAGCAUUUCCUCUCCUCCCUGGUUCCAGGCCUUUAAGAAGUGGCACCAACGCCUGGCAGCCAGGAGCCCAAGGAGAGGAGCUGCCAGUAGCCCAAGACCCUGGAGCAAGCCAGGCCCCAAGGGCCCCGAGAGUGGACAGGAAGCCGCCAGAGCACCGCGGGGUUGGGGGCUUGGGGCAGAGCAUGGGGCCCAGCUGCAGCUGUGACUUGUUCUCAUAGAAUAAAAAACAGAACUGAACUUAGCCUUCCCAGGGAAGGAACCAUGCCCCACACAUCCAGGGAGUGAUGACAGAGGGGACAGCUUGAAGAGCUCUGAAGGACAAUAAAACCCACUCCUCAGUCCUA